GCUGGGCAGGGCGACGCGGAACCGAGGCGGCGGCGGCGGCUGCGGCGGCAGGAAAUCGGGGCUCGGCCCCGCCGGCGCGCGACCCCAUCCCCAUCCCGGUCCCUGCAGAGCGAUCCCCGGGCCCAGAUAUGGACGCAGCAGAGCCGGGACUCCCCCCAGGUCCUGAGGGCAGGAAGAGGUACAGUGACAUCUUCCGGAGCCUGGACAACCUCGAAAUCUCACUGGGGAACGUGACCCUUGAGAUGCUGGCUGGAGACCCUCUACUCUCAGAAGACCCAGAACCUGACAAGACCCCUACAGCCACUGUUACCAACGAAGCCAGCUGUUGGAGCGGCCCCUCCCCAGAGGGUCCUGUACCCCUCACAGGGGAGGAACUGGACUUGCGGCUCAUUCGGACAAAGGGGGGUGUGGACGCAGCCCUGGAAUAUGCCAAGACCUGGAGCCGCUAUGCCAAGGAACUGCUUGCCUGGACUGAAAAGAGAGCCAGCUAUGAGCUGGAGUUUGCUAAGAGCACCAUGAAGAUCGCUGAAGCUGGCAAGGUGUCCAUUCAACAGCAGAGCCACAUGCCUCUGCAGUACAUCUACACCCUGUUUCUGGAGCACGAUCUCAGCCUGGGAACCCUGGCCAUGGAGACAGUGGCCCAGCAGAAAAGAGACUACUACCAGCCCCUCGCCGCCAAACGGACUGAGAUUGAGAAGUGGCGGAAGGAGUUCAAGGAGCAGUGGAUGAAGGAGCAGAAGCGGAUGAAUGAGGCGGUGCAGGCACUGCGGCGCGCCCAGCUGCAGUAUGUGCAACGCAGCGAGGACCUGCGGGCACGCUCCCAGGGGUCCCCUGAGGACUCGGCCCCCCAGGCCUCGCCGGGACCUAGCAAGCAGCAGGAGCGGCGGCGGCGCUCGCGAGAGGAGGCCCAGGCCAAGGCGCAGGAGGCCGAGGCGCUGUACCAGGCCUGUGUCCGCGAGGCCAACGCGCGGCAGCAGGACCUGGAGAUCGCCAAGCAGCGAAUCGUGUCGCACGUGCGCAAGCUGGUGUUUCAGGGGGAUGAAGUGCUGAGGCGGGUGACGCUGAGUCUCUUCGGGCUGCGGGGGGCGCAGGCAGAGCGUGGCCCCCGCGCCUUCGCCGCCCUGGCCGAGUGCUGUGCGCCCUUUGAGCCGGGCCAGCGCUACCAGGAGUUUGUACGGGCGCUGCGGCCCGAGGCCCCGCCGCCCCCGCCGCCCGCCUUCUCCUUCCAGGAGUUCCUUCCCUCCUUGAACAGCUCCCCUCUGGACAUCAGAAAGAAGCUCUCUGGGCCUCUUCCUCCAAGGCUGGAUGAGAAUUCAGCUGAGCCAGGCCCUUGGGAGGAUCCGGGCACAGGCUGGCGCUGGCAAGGGACUCCAGGCCCCACUCCGGGCAGCGAUGUGGACAGCGUGGGUGGCGGCAGCGAGUCUCGGUCCCUGGACUCACCCACUUCCAGCCCAGGCGCUGGCACGAGGCAGCUGGUGAAGGCUUCGUCCACAGGCACUGAGUCCUCAGAUGACUUUGAGGAGCGAGACCCUGACCUGGGAGACGGGCUGGAGAAUGGGCUGGGCAGCCCCUUCGGGAAGUGGACACUGUCCAGCGCGGCUCAGACCCACCAGCUGCGGCGACUGCGGGGCCCAGCCAAGUGCCGCGAGUGCGAAGCCUUCAUGGUCAGCGGGACGGAGUGUGAGGAGUGCUUUCUGACCUGCCACAAGCGCUGCCUGGAGACUCUCCUGAUCCUCUGUGGACACAGGCGGCUCCCAGCCCGGACACCCCUUUUUGGGGUUGACUUCCUGCAGCUACCCAGGGACUUCCCGGAGGAGGUACCCUUUGUGGUCACGAAGUGCACGGCUGAGAUAGAACACCGUGCCCUGGAUGUGCAGGGCAUUUACCGGGUCAGCGGGUCCCGGGUCCGUGUGGAGCGGCUGUGCCAGGCUUUCGAGAAUGGCCGAGCGUUGGUGGAGCUGUCGGGGAACUCGCCUCAUGACGUCUCGAGUGUCCUCAAGCGAUUUCUUCAGGAGCUCACCGAGCCCGUGAUCCCCUUCCACCUCUACGACGCCUUCAUCUCUCUGGCUAAGACCUUGCAUGCAGACCCUGGGGACGACCCUGGGACCCCCAGCCCCAGCCCUGAGGUUAUCCGCUCGCUGAAGACCCUCUUGGUACAGCUGCCUGACUCUAACUACAACACCCUGCGGCACCUGGUGGCCCAUCUGUUCAGGGUGGCUGCACGAUUUAUGGAAAACAAGAUGUCUGCCAACAACCUGGGCAUUGUGUUUGGGCCGACACUGCUGCGGCCGCCGGACGGCCCGCGGGCAGCCAGCGCCAUCCCUGUCACCUGCCUGCUGGACUCUGGGCAUCAGGCCCAGCUUGUGGAGUUCCUCAUCGUGCACUACGAGCAGAUCUUUGGGAUGGAUGAGCUCCCCCAGGCCACUGAGCCCCCGCCCCAAGACUCCAGCCCAGCCCCUGGGCCCCUCACAACCAGCUCCCAACCGCCACCCCCGCACCUUGACCCAGACUCCCAGCCCCCAGUCCUAGCCUCAGACCCCGGCCCAGACCCCCAGCACCACAGUACCCUGGAGCAGCAUCCCACGGCCACACCUACCGAGGUUGGAGUGCGAUGGCGUGAUCUCUGUUCACCGUAACCUCCACCUCCUGGAUUCAAGCGAUUCUCCUGCCUCAGCCUCCAGAGUAGUUGGGAUUACAGGCAUGCACCACCACACCCAGCUAAUUUUUUUUGUAUUUUUAGUAGAGUAGGGGUUUCUCCAUGUUGGUCAGGCUGGUCUCAAACUCCUGACCUCAGGCGAUCCGCCCUCCUCAGCCUCCCAAAGUGCUGGGAUUACAGGCAUGAGCCACUGCACCCGGCCUAGAAUCUUUUUUUUUUUUUUGAGAUGGAGUCUCGCUCUGUCACCCAGGCUAGAGUGCAGUGGUGCCAUCUUGGCUCACUGCAAGCUCUGCCUCCCAGGUUCACGUCAUUCUCCUGCCUCAGCCUCCCAAGUAGCUGGGACUACAGGCACCCGCCACCACACCCGGCUAAUUUUUUUGUAUUUUUAGUAGAGACGGGGUUUCACCGUGUUAGCCAGGAUGGUCUCGAUCUCCUGACCUUGUGAUCCACCCGCCUCGGCCUCCCAAAGUGCUGGGAUUACAGGCUGGAGCCACUGCACCCGGCCGCCUGGCGUAGAAUCUUUAACAAAGGUCACCAGUCUGGAUCCAGAGCUCAGCUGUGAACCAGGAAGAUAGCAGCACCCGCUGCUCCGGAUUGCUAGAACAGUCCAUGCCCAAGGCCUGUGCUGCUGGUAUCUUGCUGCAUCUGCCAUUCCUGAGAGCAAGGAUCUCUCCUGCAGCAGCCCAGAGCUGGGAAGCGGCUGCUGGUGAACUGUGGGUCUCUGAGAGCUGGAAUGCCUCAUAAAGUGCUCGGGACAGUGUCUGAUGUGUAGACACUGCCAACCAUUUAGCUAAGGAUGGAACAGUAAAGUUGGUAAGGUUGCAGAGAGCAGCCCAGGAUAGUAGUUCAGAGGCACCACCUGGUCCUAAUGUGGAGAGGGCUGAGCCACUCCCUGGGCUGGCCAUUUGCUAAACAAGGAUUUUCCCACCCUCAUGGAGCCCACGGUCCAGACUCAAUGAAUGACACUGCUCUAUGCUGGAAGGGCAAGCAGUACACUUAUUAUUAUUUUUGAGACGGAGUCUCAUUCUGUCACCCAGACUGGAGUGCAGGGGCAUGAUCUGAGCUCACUGCAAUCUCCACCUCCCAGGUCCAAGCGAUUCUCCUGCCUCAGCCUCCCUAGUAGCUGGGAUUACAGGCAUGCACCACCACGCCCGGCUAAAUUUUGUAUUUCUAGUAGAGACGGAGUUUCACCAUGUUGGCCAGGCUGGUCCCGAACUCCUGACCUCAGAUAAUCCACCAACCUCAGCCUCCCAAAGUGCUGGGAUUACAGGCAUGCACCACCAUGCCUGGCCAAGCAGUACACUUAUAAGGGCAUCGUCUAUCCCCAAACACCAAAACUGCAAAGGAUGACAGGUGCACAGUCAGUGGUGGUCCAUGCCCUGUGCAUAGGAGGAGUUCAAUGGUAGUCCACACCCAGUGCAGAGUAGGUGCAAAGUCAGGGGUGGCUGGCAGAGCCACCUGGGCCCACUCCUCUUUGGUCUCACUUCCUACCACCUUUCCCUCAUUCAUUACAGGGUGGGGCUGCGUCCUAACAUACCAGGCAUGCUCCUACCUCAGGGCCUUUGCACUGGCUAUUCCUUUUGCAUGUCCAGGAACAAGCCCUUGGCUCUCCAGGAAUCUCAAAGAACUGGGAUUUUAGUGUUGGGGUCUCAUUCUUGGGUUUCUCCCUGCAGAUUCCAACUCCACAGAGUGACCAGAGAGAGGACGUGGCUGAAGACACCAAAGAUGGGGGAGGGGAAG